GCCUCCCGAUUGACUGGCCUGCUUGGCAAGGCAAGUAGCGGCGGCGCUUCAAGAUGCGCUGCCUGACCACGCCUAUGCUGCUGCGGGCCCUGGCCCAGGCUGCACGUGCAGGACCUCCUGGUGGCCGGAGCCUCCACAGCAGUGCAGUGGCAGCCACCUACAAGUAUGUGAACAUGCAGGAUCCCGAGAUGGACAUGAAGUCAGUGACUGACCGGGCAGCCCGCACCCUGCUGUGGACUGAGCUCUUCCGAGGCCUGGGCAUGACCCUGAGCUACCUGUUCCGGGAACCGGCCACCAUCAACUACCCGUUCGAGAAGGGCCCGCUGAGCCCUCGCUUCCGUGGGGAGCAUGCGCUGCGCCGGUACCCAUCCGGGGAGGAGCGUUGCAUUGCCUGCAAGCUCUGCGAGGCCAUCUGCCCCGCCCAGGCCAUCACCAUCGAGGCUGAGCCAAGAGCUGAUGGCAGCCGCCGGACCACCCGCUAUGACAUCGACAUGACCAAGUGCAUCUACUGCGGCUUCUGCCAGGAGGCCUGUCCCGUGGAUGCCAUCGUCGAGGGCCCCAACUUUGAGUUCUCCACGGAGACCCAUGAGGAGCUGCUGUACAACAAGGAGAAGUUGCUCAACAACGGGGACAAGUGGGAGGCCGAGAUCGCCGCCAACAUCCAGGCUGACUACUUGUAUCGGUGACGCCCCACCGGCCCGCAGCCCCUGCUGCCCAAUAAAACCACUCCGACCCCA